AGAAGGCUUGGAGCCCAGACACCUGCUCACUCACCACCAGCUGGGCUCCGCCUGGGCCUGCCCGGCACCCACCCCGGCCACCAAGGGCAGCAGCUUUUCCAGAAUUUGGCUGGCAGGCCUAGUCACCCCACCUCGCCACCUCACCACUGCACCUCGGAGGCCAGCCCUGUCCACUCCACUCUGUGCCUGGCUUCUCUUGCCUGCCUUGGGCCUUCGUGUGGCCCCUCCACGGUGUCUGGGACUGAGUGCCCCUCUUGCCUCCUGAAGAGCAGCCAUGGCCACCUACAAAGUCAGGGUGGCCACAGGCACCGACCUCUUGUCGGGAACACGGGACUCCAUCUCACUGACCAUUGUGGGGACACAAGGAGAGAGCCAUAAGCAGCUGCUGAACCACUUUGGGAGAGACUUUGCAACUGGGGCGGUGGGCCAGUACACCGUGCAGUGCCCUCAGGACCUGGGUGAGCUCAUCAUCAUCCGCCUGCACAAAGAGCGGUACGCCUUCUUCCCCAAGGACCCUUGGUACUGCAACUAUGUGCAGAUCUGUGCCCCCAACGGCCGUAUCUACCACUUCCCCGCCUACCAGUGGAUGGAUGGCUACGAGACCCUGGCACUCCGGGAGGCCACAGGAAAGACAACAGCAGAUGACUCGCUCCCCGUCCUCCUGGAGCACAGAAAAGAGGAGAUCAGAGCCAAGCAGGACUUCUACCACUGGCGAGUCUUUCUUCCUGGCCUGCCCAGCUAUGUGCACAUUCCCAGUUACCGCCCUCCGGUGCGGAGGCAUCGCAACCCCAACCGGCCUGAGUGGAAUGGCUAUAUUCCGGGAUUCCCAAUUCUCAUCAACUUUAAGGCCACCAAGUUCCUGAACUUAAAUCUCCGCUACUCCUUCCUCAAGACGGCCUCCUUCUUCGUCCGCCUGGGGCCCAUGGCACUGGCUUUCAAAGUCCGCGGCCUGUUGGACUGCAAACAUUCGUGGAAGAGGCUGAAGGACAUUAGGAAAAUUUUCCCUGGCAAGAAAUCUGUCGUCUCCGAGUACGUGGCCGAGCACUGGGCAGAGGACACCUUCUUUGGGUACCAGUACCUCAACGGCGUCAACCCCGGCCUGAUCCGCCGCUGCACGCGGAUCCCAGACAAGUUCCCCGUCACAGACGACAUGGUGGCUCCGUUCCUGGGCGAGGGAACGUGCUUGCAAGCGGAGCUGGAGAAGGGGAACAUUUACCUGGCCGACUACCGCAUCAUGGAGGGCAUCCCCACCGUGGAGCUCAGCGGCCGGAAGCAGCACCACUGCGCCCCCCUCUGCCUGCUGCACUUUGGACCCGAGGGCAAGAUGAUGCCCAUCGCCAUCCAGCUCAGCCAGACCCCUGGGCCAGAUUGCCCCAUCUUCCUGCCCAGUGAUUCUGAGUGGGACUGGCUGCUAGCCAAGACGUGGGUACGCUAUGCGGAGUUCUACAGCCACGAGGCCAUCGCCCACCUGCUGGAGACACACCUCAUUGCUGAGGCCUUCUGCCUGGCCUUGCUGAGGAACCUGCCCAUGUGCCACCCCCUCUACAAGCUCCUCAUCCCCCAUACCCGAUACACCGUCCAGAUCAACAGCAUUGGCCGGGCCGUUCUCCUCAAUGAGGGGGGGCUCUCUGCCAAGGGCAUGUCCCUGGGCGUGGAAGGCUUUGCUGGGGUGAUGGUACGGGCUCUGUCGGAGCUCACCUAUGACAGCCUCUACCUCCCCAAUGACUUUGUGGAGCGUGGGGUCCAGGACCUGCCUGGAUAUUACUACCGCGAUGACAGCUUGGCGGUGUGGAAUGCACUGGAGAAGUAUGUGACGGAGAUCAUCACCUAUUAUUACCCGAGUGACGCAGCCGUGGAGGGUGAUCCGGAAUUGCAGUCUUGGGUGCAGGAAAUAUUUAAAGAGUGCCUCCUGGGGCGGGAGAGCUCAGGCUUCCCUAGGUGCUUGCGAACCGUGCCUGAGCUGAUCCGAUAUGUCACUAUAGUCAUCUACACCUGCUCUGCCAAGCACGCUGCUGUCAACACAGGCCAGAUGGAGUUCACCGCCUGGAUGCCCAACUUCCCAGCGUCCAUGCGGAAUCCACCGAUUCAGACUAAGGGGCUGACCACUCUGGAGACCUUCAUGGACACGUUGCCGGAUGUGAAGACCACGUGCAUCACGCUGCUGGUGCUCUGGACCCUCAGCCGAGAGCCUGACGACAGGCGGCCCCUGGGACACUUCCCGGACAUUCACUUCGUGGAGGAGGCCCCGCGGAGGAGCAUAGAGGCGUUCCGCCAGCGCCUGAACCAGAUCUCACACGACAUCCGCCAGCGCAACAAGUGCCUUCCCAUCCCCUACUACUACCUGGACCCGGUGCUGAUUGAGAACAGCAUUUCUAUUUAGGAGCGCGCUUCCCGUCUCUCCUCUCCCCAUUCUGUGCCCUACUAUUUUCAACAAAACAAAACAAACAAGCAAAAAACACAAAAACCUCAGAGACCAAAACACCAAACAAACAAAAAAACAAAAAACCUUCCUUUC